CACAGUGGUUCACUCACCCCUCCUCCCACCUCGGCAGCCCUGGGAUGUCGCUGCUGACUCAGGAGGAACCCGAGGUGCCGUAGCGGCUGCUCCAAUAUUGCAGAAGAGGUUCCUCAGGCAGCUCUGCCCACAGCCCCAAGUCACGAAUUCCGUGACUCCAGCUCCAUCCCAGGCCCCAGGGUACCUGGCCCAGGGUUGUGCUGCCGCAGACUUGGCCUGUACCAUCCAGGCGGCGGUGGGGAGCUGGGGUUGGAAAGGCUUCUUGGAGUGGACUCCUGGGUCUGUCUGGGAGACGGGGAGGAAGGGACACUCUGAACAUCACCAGGGGCUGCUGGGGGGCCCUGGCCACCCCCAGAGUCAGAACAGGCAGGUGGGGCAGGAUCUCAGGUCAUCCUAUGCUACACUCAGCCAUUGCGUGGCCCCUCUCCUCCCUGUGCCUGGCCUUUUGGCCAGCCCUGGGGCCACCGAGAGGAUGCAGCACCGAACCCUCCAGGAGCCCCCAGUGCUGCCGUCUGUGGGACAGGGACAAUCCCAUCCCCACUGCUACUGUCUGUGCUGUGCUGGGCACAGAGCUGGACACCUCCAAGGCCCAGCGCCCGUAGUGGCUCUCAUCAUGGACAAUUCACAGGCAGAUGGUGGCCAGCUCUGUGGCCUGCAGGGACUGGGAGCGGCGCCAGACCAUCUAGGCCCCAACCUAUCUGCAUUAUCCUGGAAGACUUCCUGGAGGAGGCUUCUAAGCUGAGGCCCAAGGACCAUGUCAGGUCUAGGACUAGGACCAGUGCAGGCCGAGGCCAGAGAGACAGCUGGGCUUCCAGAACCGUACGGAGUCCCCAGAACCUAAUGCCACAGCGACCCCUGCGAUCCCCACUAUCCUGGUGACCUCUGUGACCUCUGAGACCCCAGCAACAAGUGCUCCAGAGGCAGAGGGACCCCAAAGUGGGGGGCUCCCGCCCCCGCCCAGGGCAGUUCCCUCGAGCAGUAGCCCCCAGGCCCAAGCACUCACCGAGGACGGGAGGCCCUGCAGGUUCCCCUUCCGCUACGGGGGCCGCAUGCUGCAUGCCUGCACUUCGGAGGGCAGUGCACACAGGAAGUGGUGUGCCACAACUCACAACUACGACCGGGACAGGGCCUGGGGCUACUGUGUGGAGGCCACCCCGCCUCCAGGGGGCCCAGCUGCCCUGGAUCCCUGUGCCUCCGGCCCCUGCCUCAAUGGAGGCUCCUGCUCCAAUACCCAGGACCCCCAGUCCUAUCACUGCAGCUGCCCCCGGGCCUUCACCGGCAAGGACUGCGGCACAGAGAAAUGCUUUGAUGAGACCCGCUACGAGUACCUGGAGGGGGGCGACCGCUGGGCCCGCGUGCGCCAGGGCCACGUGGAACAGUGCGAGUGCUUCGGGGGCCGGACCUGGUGCGAAGGCACCCGACAUACAGCUUGUCUGAGCAGCCCUUGCCUGAACGGGGGCACCUGCCACCUGAUCGUGGCCACCGGGACCACCGUGUGUGCCUGCCCACCAGGCUUCGCUGGACGGCUCUGCAACAUCGAGCCUGAUGAGCGCUGCUUCUUGGGGAACGGCACUGGGUACCGUGGCGUGGCCAGCACCUCAGCCUCGGGCCUCAGCUGCCUGGCCUGGAACUCCGAUCUGCUCUACCAGGAGCUGCACGUGGACUCCGUGGGCGCCGCGGCCCUGCUGGGCCUGGGCCCCCAUGCCUACUGCCGGAAUCCGGACAAUGACGAGAGGCCCUGGUGCUACGUGGUGAAGGACAGCGCGCUCUCCUGGGAGUACUGCCGCCUGGAGGCCUGCGAAUCCCUCACCAGAGUCCAACUGUCACCGGAUCUCCUGGCGACCCUGCCUGAGCCAGCCUCCCCGGGGCGCCAGGCCUGCGGCAGGAGGCACAAGAAGAGGACGUUCCUGCGGCCACGUAUCAUCGGCGGCUCCUCCUCGCUGCCCGGCUCGCACCCCUGGCUGGCCGCCAUCUACAUCGGGGACAGCUUCUGCGCCGGGAGCCUGGUCCACACCUGCUGGGUGGUGUCGGCCGCCCACUGCUUCUCCCACAGCCCCCCCAGGGACAGCGUCUCCGUGGUGCUGGGCCAGCACUUCUUCAACCGCACGACGGACGUGACGCAGACCUUCGGCAUCGAGAAGUACAUCCCGUACACCCUGUACUCGGUGUUCAACCCCAGCGACCACGACCUCGUCCUGAUCCGGCUGAAGAAGAAAGGGGACCGCUGUGCCACACGCUCGCAGUUCGUGCAGCCCAUCUGCCUGCCCGAGCCCGGCAGCACCUUCCCCGCAGGACACAAGUGCCAGAUUGCGGGCUGGGGCCACUUGGAUGAGAACGUGAGCGGCUACUCCAGCUCCCUGCGGGAGGCCCUGGUCCCCCUGGUCGCCGACCACAAGUGCAGCAGCCCUGAGGUCUACGGCGCCGACAUCAGCCCCAACAUGCUCUGUGCCGGCUACUUCGACUGCAAGUCCGACGCCUGCCAGGGGGACUCAGGGGGGCCCCUGGCCUGCGAGAAGAACGGCGUGGCUUACCUCUACGGCAUCAUCAGCUGGGGUGACGGCUGCGGGCGGCUCCACAAGCCGGGGGUCUACACCCGCGUGGCCAACUAUGUGGACUGGAUCAACGACCGGAUACGGCCUCCCAGGCGGCUUGUGGCUCCCUCCUGACCCUCCAGCGGGACACCCUGGUUCCCACCAUUCCCUGCCUUGCUGACAAUAAAGAUAUUUCCAAGAA